CGGAGCUCCUCAGACCCGGCGGGACCCCAGGCGCACCCUGGAGCUGCAGACCCCCGGCCCCGUCCCACGGCUAGCUGAAUCGUGAGAUCCUGGCUCAGGGACGCUCAGCUGGUCAGCAGUCCUAUUGGGACCUGUGACAACUUAGGGCUUCUGGCUACCGAAACUAUCUUCAUUUCCACUUAAAAAGUAUACGAUUUAGCUAGAAACGAACGAGUUGUGACCGCAGCUUUCCACUUUUGGUUUAUUUGAAUUGGUGUCUCUUCCUGGCGUCUACUGAUACUUGGUCAGGGAAUAUAAAAUUAAUUUACUUAUCCAACAACCGAAAAAGGAUAUAAUUAUUUUUAAAAAGUAAUCUGCUUCAAGGUCAAGAACAUGAUUUUCUAAUUAACUGCUGUUUUUGGUUUCAUAGUCACACUUUCUUCAUGGGCCCGAAUAAUUGAAUAGACCGUGUGUAAUGAAAUUUACAUUUGAAAUGUGAAUAAAAUAAUUUUUGCAGUCUUGGAAAUUUUGAGGUCCCAAAUUUAUUUCGUAUGCCACACAAGAACUUUCAUGCGCGUCCGUGUGAAGAGACCACCAAACAGGCUUUGUAAAUCUCCUUUACAGACAAUAGGUGAAGAACAAACCCAGAAUCCCUACACUGAACUGCUAGUACUGAAGGCUCAUCAUGAUAUUGUACGAUUUCUGGUACAGUUAGAUGACUACAGAUUUGCAUCUGCUGGUGAUGAUGGAAUUGUAGUUGUGUGGAAUGCCCAGACAGGGGAAAAACUUUUAGAACUGAAUGGACACACUCAAAAGAUAACAGCUAUUAUUACAUUUCCUUCCUUGGAAUCUUGUGAAGAGAAAAAUCAACUCAUCUUGACAGCCUCUGCUGAUAGAACAGUUAUUGUGUGGGAUGGUGAUACUACCAGACAAGUUCAGAGAAUAUCAUGCUUCCAGUCUACUGUAAAGUGUUUAACUGUUCUUCAGAGACUAGAUGUUUGGCUUUCUGGUGGGAAUGACCUGUGUGUGUGGAACCGAAAAUUAGAUCUCCUGUGUAAGACUAGCCACCUUUCUGAUACAGGUAUUAGUGCUUUGGUUGAAAUACCUAAGAACUGUGUUGUGGCAGCAGUUGGCAAAGAACUGAUAAUUUUCAGGUUGGUAGCACCCACAGAAGGAUCACUAGAAUGGGAUAUUCUUGAAGUUAAGCGCCUCCUUGAUCACCAGGAUAAUAUUCUCUCAUUGAUUAAUGUCAAUGAUUUGAGUUUUGUCACCGGCUCCCACGUCGGAGAGCUGAUCAUCUGGGAUGCCCUGGACUGGACCAUGCAGGCCUAUGAACGCAACUUCUGGGACCCAUCUCCACAACUGGACACCCAACAAGAAAUAAAACUCUGUCAAAAAUCAAAUGACAUUUCUAUUCAUCAUUUCACAUGUGAUGAAGAGAAUGUAUUUGCUGCAGUUGGAAGGGGUUUAUACGUGUAUAGCCUUCAAAUGAAGCGUGUGAUUGCCUGCCAGAAAACUGCACAUGACUCCAAUGUCCUGCACGUUGCCAGACUUCCAAACAGGCAGUUAAUCUCAUGCUCAGAAGAUGGCAGUGUACGCAUUUGGGAGUUAAGAGAAAAACAGCAGCUUGCAGCUGAGCCUGUACCAACAGGUUUUUUUAACAUGUGGGGAUUUGGAAGAGUCAGCAAACAAGCCAGCCAACCUGUUAAAAAGCAGCAAGAAAAUGCUACUUCAUGUUCACUGGAGCUUAUUGGAGAUUUGAUUGGACACUCAUCAUCUGUGGAGAUGUUUCUAUACUUUGAAGAUCAUGGACUAGUGACGUGCUCCGCUGAUCAUCUCAUUAUUUUGUGGAAAAAUGGAGAGCGAGAAUCUGGAUUGCGCAGUUUAAGAUUAUUUCAAAAAUUAGAGGAGAAUGGUGACUUAUACCUUGCUGUCUAGUUUAAGGAAUUAAAAAUACACAUGCAUGAACCUUGAACAUCAAAUAUCGGGUACUACUCUGAAAACCAUUAAUAUAUUGAUCACUUAAAUUGGUAAUUUUUUUUGUCAGUCCAUAAAAUUCUACAUGUUUAAAUUUUUUGUGGACCUACCAACCAGGAACAUGUUGCUUCUCAGGUCCUAGUAUAUCCUCCAAAGAAUAUACCACAAGUUUUUCCAUUUGACUUUGAGCUGCUGUUGAAGUGGUGAGUGCUGUGUUUUGAGCUUAUUUUGAACCUAGAUCCUUGUGAAAGGUACAAAUAGAGGUAAUAGUUAAGUUAUGGCAUUUAUUAGAAGUUUUAUUAUUUGGCUUCCUUUAGAAUUAUUGUGAAGUUUAAAAAUAGCCUUUCUCCUGCAAAUUUUCCUAGUCUUUAGUAACUGUUAGUGUUCUAUAUAGCACAAACUUGAAUCUCUCAGCCAAAAAAGGGAACAUAUAUACUGUUUAAGUAUGGCAAGUUUUCUUUGGUACCAAUUUGUUUAGAUAAUUUUAAAAAUGUUUUUUAGUUCUAGCUACUAAAACCUGUAUGAACUCAAAUGGAUAGGCAUCUUGUGAGGGUGUGUUUUUCCCAGUGUGAAUUGGCUUGAAGAGCCAUGGGCUAAAUGGGUACUAGAACAACAACUGCCCCUCAUGUACGCCAAGGAUGAGCUCUAGAUCAUUUGAGAGGCACAGUGUUUCCGGAGUCAGGGACUGCAGCUGAGCGCAACUGCCCCAUCUGACCACUGACUCAAAUACGAACUGCUUGAGACAGACUUCUUUUAUGUAGUUCUUUGCAGUGUCCAUUGAGACACUAUAACCAGCCUUGUAACAAUAUGUUUUCUCCUUUUGGUGCUAAAAAAUGAAAAUAUUAGAAAGUAGUCUACACAUUAAAGAUUGAAAUUCUUAAACUACUGAUGAAGAAAGGGCAACGUGACAGAUGUUAGCAGACUGACCCUUCUUACAGAAAACCUACAGAUUUAUUUGUUCAUUAUACAAAUAUACUACAAAUAUACCCUAAAGGGAAUCUCCAUAAGUUCUUUUACUAGUUUUAGCUUUGACAGUUGCUUCCACAACUACCUACAAAGACUGGAAGAGUUAAGGUCAUCUGAGUAGACCAGUGGCAUAAUGUUACAAAUGAGGAAACUGAGGCCCAGUGCAGUAAGGCCUUGCAAUUAAAUCUGUAGUGCCCAGUAUCACCAAGCAGCUCUAAAAACAGGAACUGAAGACUGAAUGAGAAAAGGCUUAUAUGACUACUUUAAAUCCAAACAACAUUGAGUCAUGAAAAGUUCUAUGGAGAAAUAUUAAAACUUAAGCUACCUCAAUUACAGAAGACUUUCUCCCAUUAUUCACGUGCUUUUUCCUUUAGAAAUUCUGCAUUGGCCCAUACAUUUGUAAAGUUGUUUUCUGAAGUUGUAUGACACAAGGGAGCCAUAGACUUAACUGUUUUACUUCCUAGCCUGUUCUAGGCUAGUAUUUUGUGAUAGUAAUCUAUUCAAAUGGAGUGGUAGAAAUCACAUGAAUUUUGGAAGCAAAUGGUACCGUAAGUACCACAGCAAAUUCCUUCUGGUCAUUAUACAGGCGUACCUCAGAGAUACUACAGGUUAGGUUUCAGACCACAUCAAAAAAGCAACUAUUGCAAAUAGAGUGAGUCACAUCUAGUUUUUGGUUUCCCAGUGCCUAUAAAACUUGUGUUUAUACUACAGUCUUAAAUUUCUAAAAAAUGUACAUACCUUAAGAAUACUUUAUUGCUAAAAAAUGCUAACAAUCAUCUGAGCCUUCAGCGAGUCAUAAUCUUUUUGCUGGUGGAGGGUCUUGAUACUGCUGGCUGUUGACUAAGGUGGUUACUGAAGGUUGGGGUGGCUGUGGCAGUUCCUUAAAAUAAGAUAGCGAUGAAGUUUUCCAAAUCAAUUGACUUCCUUUCACAAAUGAGAUCUCUGUAACAUGUAAUACUAUUUAAUAGCAUUUUACCCACAGUAGAACUUCUUUCAAAAUUUAGAGUCUGUCAUCUCAAAUCCUGAUGCUCCUUUAUGAACUAAGUUUAUAGAAUAUUCUAAAUCCUUUGUUGUCAUUUCAACUAUGUUUACAGCAUCUUCACUGUGGAAAUGACUGUCUCCAGAAACCACUUUCUAUACACAUUCUUAAGCAACUUCUCAUCUAUUAAAGUUUGAUCAUGAGAUUACAGCAAUUCA